AGACAUCCUUGGGGAGCCUGCCCUUUCAAGCAUGAAUCAUACCACCAGAGAUCACCCAGCGUGCUCUUAGCUCUGCCUGCCUGGUGUAGGGUCCUGGAGACCUUCUUGGAGCUCAUCCAGCAGCCAUCAUGCAAGGUGGUGCUGGGGACUGCCCUCUUGCUAGGAGGUGGAGGUCUCAUGCUGUGGGUUCAGAGAAAGAGGAGAAGAAAGGAAACCUCUGAGUGUCCAUCAGACAAGGACAAGUCACCAGAAUCCCAUAAAGCAAAGAAUGAAAGCUGGAUUAAAUCCCACUUUAGCCGCCUUUCCGAAGAGAAGCUGGCCCUCGACAACAAUGCCAGCGCUAGUGGCAAUGCUACCCAGACUGAGAGUGGGAGUGAAGAGGUCAGCUCCACGGUUCACAUAGAGACCUUCACCACGAGGCACGGAGAAGUGGGCUCCGCUCUGCACCGGGAAUCCUUCACCAGCAGGCAGAAGACAUCUGGGCCCUCAGUGAUCCAAGAGAUCCACCAGGAGUCUGGAAAAGCCCCAUCCACUGAUGAGGCCACGUGGGCCGCUGUGGCUGCCUGCACCAAGGAGAUUGACACCCAGGGGCGGCACCUGGCUCACUCCAUGCUGCAGCGGGCCAUAGCUUACCAGCACUCAGGUCACCUAGAGUCCAAGGACAUCAACCAGGAGGAGCUGAGGGCCCUCGAGGAGGUAGAGAUGAAGCUGCAAAAGAAUUUCCUCACCCAGCGGGAAAACACCAUAGCUGGUGCCAAUCACACACACACCUUCUAUGGCCACAGUCACCACAGUCACCAUGGCCACCCAAGCCACCAGAGCCACAGCCUGCCUAAUCGCAGACACUAGAUCUGUGACUUCUUGGAAGCCACCUAACCAUGGAUGGAGACGCCCCUGCCCCCAGCAAGGCUGGCUCACACACACGUCUGUUUUCUCUCCUAUGGGGCCAUCUAUGCAGGCCAGGGUGAGAUGCUGUGCCCAAAUCCCUACUUUCUUAGGCUCCUCACGGGGAUUAUGGGCUCUUUAAACUCCAUGAGUGGGGUCUGCCACAGAAGAUGGCCCCUGUUGGAGGGAGAGCUGGGAGGACACAGCGCAGGUGAGAUAGACCCUGAGGCCCCUGAAGACCCACCAAGAGAAGACAGAUGGGAGCAGGCAAGAGCCCCACACUGAUGUCAUUGCCUGGAACGGAGCCAAUAAAGCUUUGUGUGCCUUCA